CCUCGCUUCCUCCGCGGUCUUCCGAGCGGUCGCGUGAACUGCUUCCUGCAGGCUGGCCAUGGCGCUUCACGUUCCCAAGGCUCCGGGCUUUGCCCAGAUGCUCAAGGAGGGAGCGAAAGUAAGGGCUGAAGGAAAGGAAUGAGGUGGGAGCGUCAGCAUAGGGCUGCGGCGGCCGCGGCGAAGUAGGAGGGCCUACUAACGGGCUGAGCGUGCUGCCCUGGCUCAGCGGCCGGGGGAAGAGAAGAUUCCAGAAAGGGAGGUGAUUUUGGAAGGGCUCGGCCACCGGAGCCUGCGGGCACUUCUCUUCUUCCGCGACCGGGAGAAGGCCGAGGGAUCGGCGGCACGAUCGACAUUGUACACCUUGAAGGUGGACGGAUGUGAAGCCGCGCGUGCGUUUUGCCUCCAUCCGUAAAUGGGGCUAAGGCCCGUCACCCUUAAAGGAGGUUGUGAGGGUGAAAUUGAAUAACGUAGAUGAAAUUGUCUUGAGAACUGCGACGUCGAUUAUCACAUAGCUCGCGAGUUGUAGGAUGGGGAAGAACGAGAACUAGCCGAUCCAGAGAAGAGAGUGGGAAAAAGGGCCGGGUCUUGGUUGCUUGCUUCCCAGUGAGAAACAUACGGCUUUCAGCUUAGUUGACAGAAGCCAUGCGUUGUAGCCAAAUGAGUUCCGGUCCCAACUUAUGUUAGCUGGCUUAAUCUAAAAUGUAACUUUCUUGGGUUUUGUUUCCUUCGUCUUUAAAUUAUGGAGAUUGGACCAAGAGGUGGUGUCUUUGAGUUCUGUGUAAUCUGCAGGAUAAGUGAUAGAGGGGUGCAGAUAACACUUUUGUUUAAUGGCCUUUUCUUGAACGUUAGUUCGGUAGCAUAGUUUUAAAAAAUAUCUUACUGCACUAUUGAUAAAUUUGUCUCUUGUGCUAUUCAAAUUGCAUUCCUCUGUGUGUCCUCCAGAUUUUGUUAAUUCAAGAAAUAGAUCAGUGUGGUUGAAUUUAAGGUUUUAUGCGAGGUACGGGGAGCAUUAACAGUUUAAUAGAACUAGGUUCAUGUUUGUAGGAUGCACUUUUCAAAUAAUGUCGGUAUAGUAAGUAAAUGUCAGGGUUCAAGGUAAAUGUUGGUGGAAUAAUCUUUUGAAAAUGAUAUGGGCUGAUUCCCUUGAAAAAAUCAGGCUGAGAUAAUAGCUUCCAAUUUGGGUUUUUUUCACUAAUACAGUUUUGGAAAACUCGUGUAUCACAAAACAUUAUUUGUCAUUCCAGUGCUAGUAGUUUUUUACAGAACACUGAGCUAUUUCUUUCAAUAAAUAGGUACUGAAGGAACUGCAGUGAAAGACAAAAGUCCCAUUUGUCGUAGAGUUUAUGUCCUUCUAAGGCAGAAAUAAUGAUUAAAUAAAAGGAGAAUUCCAAAUAAUGAUGAAAGAAACUGCACUAUAGUAGAGGAUGACAGGAGGUAAAAAUGUCUGUAAAAGAAGGAUCAGGAAUAGACAGAACACUUAGACGUUUAGGGAAGAACUCUUAGCUCAGUGCUUAGUGAGAGAAGCCCCUGAGCCUGGGCUGUUUCCCCCGACCUCUUACUUAGGGGGAAAUGCCAGGCUCAGGGACUAACUAGUACAAAGACCCUGAGGAAGGAAUGAUUUUGACCUGUUUUUUUUUUAAAACAACAACAACAACAACAGGUUGUAGGGCUGAAGCUUACCAAAGAAAGGAAGAAUGCACUUUUCAGGAUUAGAAGAGGCUGUGUAUAGAAACAUACAAGCUUGCAAGGAGCUUGCCCAAACCACUCGUACAGCAUAUGGACCAAAUGGAAUGAACAAAAUGGUUAUCAACCACUUGGAGAAGUUGUUUGUGACAAACGAUGCAGCAACUAUUUUAAGAGAACUAGAAGUACAGCAUCCUGCUGCAAAAAUGAUUGUAAUGGCUUCUCAUAUGCAAGAGCAAGAAGUUGGAGAUGGCACAAACUUUGUUCUGGUAUUUGCUGGAGCUCUCCUGGAAUUAGCUGAAGAACUUCUGAGGAUUGGCCUGUCAGUUUCAGAGGUCAUAGAAGGUUAUGAAAUAGCCUGCAGAAAAGCUCAUGAGAUUCUUCCUAAUUUGGUAUGUUGUUCUGCAAAAAACCUUCGAGAUAUUGAUGAAGUCUCAUCUCUACUUCGUACCUCCAUAAUGAGUAAACAAUAUGGUAAUGAAGUAUUUCUGGCCAAGCUUAUUGCUCAGGCAUGCGUAUCUAUUUUUCCUGAUUCCGGCCAUUUCAAUGUUGAUAACAUCAGAGUUUGUAAAAUUCUGGGCUCUGGUAUCAGUUCCUCUUCAGUAUUGCAUGGCAUGGUUUUUAAGAAGGAAACCGAAGGUGAUGUAACAUCUGUCAAAGAUGCAAAAAUAGCAGUGUACUCUUGUCCUUUUGAUGGCAUGAUAACAGAAACUAAGGGAACAGUGUUGAUAAAGACUGCUGAAGAAUUGAUGAAUUUUAGUAAGGGAGAAGAAAACCUCAUGGAUGCACAAGUCAAAGCUAUUGCUGAUACUGGUGCAAAUGUCGUAGUAACAGGUGGCAAAGUGGCAGACAUGGCUCUUCAUUAUGCAAAUAAAUAUAAUAUCAUGUUAGUGAGGCUAAACUCAAAAUGGGAUCUCCGAAGACUUUGUAAAACUGUUGGUGCUACAGCUCUUCCUAGAUUGACACCUCCUGUCCUUGAAGAAAUGGGACACUGUGACAGUGUUUACCUCUCAGAAGUUGGAGAUACUCAGGUGGUGGUUUUUAAGCAUGAAAAGGAAGAUGGCGCCAUUUCUACCAUAGUACUUCGAGGCUCUACAGACAAUCUGAUGGAUGACAUAGAAAGGGCAGUAGACGAUGGUGUUAAUACUUUCAAAGUUCUUACAAGGGAUAAACGUCUUGUACCCGGAGGUGGAGCAACAGAAAUUGAAUUAGCCAAACAGAUCACAUCAUAUGGAGAGACAUGUCCUGGACUUGAACAGUAUGCUAUUAAGAAGUUUGCUGAGGCAUUUGAAGCUAUUCCCCGCGCACUGGCAGAAAACUCUGGAGUUAAGGCCAAUGAAGUAAUCUCUAAACUUUAUGCAGUACAUCAAGAAGGAAAUAAAAACGUUGGAUUAGAUAUUGAGGCUGAAGUCCCUGCUGUAAAGGACAUGCUGGAAGCUGGUAUUCUAGAUACUUACCUGGGAAAAUAUUGGGCUAUCAAACUCGCUACUAAUGCUGCAGUCACUGUACUUAGAGUGGAUCAGAUCAUCAUGGCAAAACCAGCUGGUGGGCCCAAGCCUCCAAGUGGGAAGAAAGACUGGGAUGAUGACCAAAAUGAUUGAAAUUGGCUUAAUUUUUACUGUAGGUGAAGGCUGUAUUUGUAGUAGUACUCAAGAAUCACCUGAUGUUUUCUUAUUCUCCUUAAAUUAAGAGUUAUUUUGUGUUUGUAUUCUUGGCUGGAUGUUAUAAUAAACAUAUUGUUACUGUCAAA